ACUCCCGGCUUCCAACCGCGCGGAGCCUCUGCCUUGGAGAUUCUCAGUGCUGCGGAUCAUGUCCCUAAGGGGCAGCCUCUCGCGUCUCCUCCAGACGCGAGUGCAUUCCAUCCUGAAGAAAUCCGUCCACUCCGUGGCUGUGAUAGGAGCCCCGUUCUCACAAGGGCAGAAAAGAAAAGGAGUGGAGCAUGGUCCCGCUGCCAUAAGAGAAGCUGGCUUGAUGAAAAGGCUCUCCAGUUUGGGCUGCCACCUAAAAGACUUUGGAGAUUUGAGUUUUACUCCAGUCCCCAAAGAUGAUCUCUACAACAACCUGAUAGUGAAUCCACGCUCAGUGGGUCUUGCCAACCAGGAACUGGCUGAGGUGGUUAGCAGAGCUGUGUCAGAUGGCUACAGCUGUGUCACACUGGGAGGAGACCACAGCCUGGCAAUCGGUACCAUUAGUGGCCAUGCCCGACACUGCCCAGACCUUUGUGUUGUCUGGGUUGAUGCCCAUGCUGACAUCAACACACCCCUUACCACUUCAUCAGGAAAUCUCCAUGGACAGCCAGUUUCAUUUCUCCUCAGAGAACUACAGGAUAAGGUACCACAACUCCCAGGAUUUUCCUGGAUCAAACCUUGUAUCUCUUCUGCAAGUAUUGUGUAUAUUGGUCUGAGAGACGUGGACCCUCCUGAACAUUUUAUUUUAAAGAACUAUGAUAUCCAGUAUUUUUCCAUGAGAGAUAUUGAUCGACUUGGUAUCCAGAAGGUCAUGGAACGAACAUUUGAUCUGCUGAUUGGCAAGAGACAAAGACCAAUCCAUUUGAGUUUUGAUAUUGAUGCAUUUGACCCUACACUGGCUCCAGCCACAGGAACUCCUGUUGUCGGGGGACUAACCUAUCGAGAAGGCAUGUAUAUUGCUGAGGAAAUACACAAUACAGGGUUGCUAUCAGCACUGGAUCUUGUUGAAGUCAAUCCUCAGUUGGCCACCUCAGAGGAAGAGGCGAAGACUACAGCUAACCUGGCAGUAGAUGUGAUUGCUUCAAGCUUUGGUCAGACAAGAGAAGGAGGGCAUAUUGUCUAUGACCAACUUCCUACUCCCAGUUCACCAGAUGAAUCAGAAAAUCAAGCACGUGUGAGAAUUUAGGAGACACUGUGCACUGACAUGUUUCACAACAGGCAUUCCAGAAUUAUGAGGCAUUGAGGGGAUAGAUGAAUACUAAAUGGUUGUCUGGGUCAAUACUGCCUUAAUGAGAACAUUUACACAUUCUCACAAUUGUAAAGUUUCCCCUCUAUUUUGGUGACCAAUACUACUGUAAAUGUAUUUGGUUUUUUGCAGUUCACAGGGUAUUAAUAUGCUACAGUACUAUGUAAAUUUAAAGAAGUCAUAAACAGCAUUUAUUACCUUGGUAUAUCAUACUGGUCUUGUUGCUGUUGUUCCUUCACAUUUAAGUGGUUUUUCAUCUUUCCUCCCUCCUCCCACAGCCUGGCUAUACAGUGCAUCCUUGAACUGUCAGCCCACAGCAGCAAUAUGCUUAUUCUAUCCACAUCCCUAACAUCAUGCAUUCACAAGGUCAAAGUUCUGGUCCACAAACCCUUCCCUAUAGAAGUUCAAUGGCUGCGAAAGAAUUUGUAGUAAACCAGGCCUCCCAGGAUGGCGAGCUCCAGUAAGAUGAUAAUGGAAAGCAGCAGCUUGUUGGUUGUCACUCUACAAAGAGAAGCAAAGUGGGGAGUAGUCAGAAGUUUGGAUAACCUUCCUUCUAAACAUUUUGGGGUUAGACCUGGGACCACGGCUGGAUACUCUGAGGCUGUAUGUUUGAUCACACAGCCACUUAGCAGGAAGUACUCAUAAGGUUCUUUAGCUGUCACUUAGGGAUAACACUGUCUACCUCACAGAAAUGUUAAACUGAGACAAUAAAAACCAAAGCAUAAAAA